GCCAGUCCUCGGCUGCGCUCACCGGUAGGCCCCGCUCGGGUUCCGCCGAAGCCCAGCCCCCGCAGGUCGCCCCUCCGACGCCGGCGCGCCGCAAGGGAGGCCAGCUCGCUCGCAGUGGGGAGGUCGCGGCUCCAGUCCUCGCGUCCCCGCCGUGGUCCCGGUGCCUGUCCCAUCCCGCGGGCGCGGCCGUUGCGGGCGGCGCGGCCCGGGCGCGCGCGGCGAAUCUGCGGCUGCGAAUCGGCUGGAGCGGGGCCUCGCGAGAGCGGCGAGGCCUGGGCGGCUGGGCCUGGGCGGGCGGCGCGGGCUGCUCCGGAGGCUCGGGUGGCUUGAGAGUCUUGGGAGGCUCCGGGCGCUGCCCGCGCGGUCGCCGGCAUGACGGGCCGCGUGUGCCGCGGUUGCGGCGGCACGGACAUCGAGCUGGACGCGGCGCGCGGGGACGCGGUGUGCACCGCCUGCGGCUCAGUGCUGGAGGACAACAUCAUCGUGUCCGAGGUGCAGUUCGUGGAGAGCAGCGGCGGCGGCUCCUCGGCCGUGGGCCAGUUCGUGUCCCUGGACGGUGCUGGCAAAACCCCGACUCUGGGUGGCGGCUUCCACGUGAAUCUGGGGAAGGAGUCGAGAGCGCAGACCCUGCAGAAUGGGAGGCGCCACAUCCACCACCUGGGGAACCAGCUGCAGCUGAACCAGCACUGCCUGGACACCGCCUUCAACUUCUUCAAGAUGGCCGUGAGCAGGCACCUGACCCGCGGCCGGAAGAUGGCCCACGUGAUUGCUGCCUGCCUCUACCUGGUCUGCCGUACGGAGGGCACGCCGCACAUGCUCCUGGACCUCAGCGACCUGCUCCAGGUGAAUGUGUACGUGCUUGGAAAGACGUUUCUUCUCUUGGCAAGAGAGCUCUGCAUCAAUGCGCCGGCCAUAGACCCGUGCCUGUAUAUUCCACGCUUUGCGCACCUGCUGGAAUUCGGGGAGAAGAACCACGAGGUGUCCAUGACUGCCCUGAGGCUCCUACAGAGGAUGAAGCGGGACUGGAUGCACACAGGCCGGCGCCCCUCGGGCCUCUGCGGAGCAGCGCUCCUGGUUGCAGCCAGAAUGCAUGACUUCAGGAGGACUGUGAAGGAGGUCAUCAGUGUGGUCAAAGUGUGUGAGUCCACGCUGCGGAAGAGGCUCACGGAAUUUGAAGACACCCCCACCAGUCAGUUGACCAUUGAUGAGUUCAUGAAGAUCGACCUGGAGGAGGAGUGCGACCCCCCCUCGUACACAGCUGGGCAGAGGAAGCUGCGGAUGAAGCAGCUUGAACAAGUCCUGUCAAAAAAACUGGAGGAGGUUGAAGGUGAAAUAUCCAGUUACCAGGAUGCAAUUGAGAUUGAACUAGAAAACAGCCGGCCAAAGGCCAAGGGGGGCCUGGCCAGCCUGGCAAAAGAUGGCUCCACCGAGGACACCGCGUCCAGCUUGUGUGGCGAGGAGGACACAGAGGACGAGGAGCUGGAAGCCGCGGCCAGCCACCUGAACAAAGACUUAUACCGGGAGCUCCUUGGUGGUGCCCCCGGCAGCUCGGAAGCAGCAGGAAGCCCCGAGUGGGGCGGCAGACCUCCGGCCCUGGGGUCCCUGCUGGACCCCCUCCCCACUGCAGCCAGCCUGGGCAUCUCAGACUCCAUCCGCGAAUGCAUCUCCUCUCAGAGCAGCGACCCCAAAGAUGCUUCAGGAGACGGUGAGCUGGACCUCAGUGGCAUUGAUGACCUGGAGAUUGACAGGUACAUCCUGAAUGAGUCGGAAGCCCGCGUGAAGGCCGAGCUGUGGAUGAGGGAGAACGCCGAGUACCUGCGGGAACAGAGGGAAAAAGAAGCAAGAAUAGCGAAAGAGAAGGAGCUCGGCAUCUACAAGGAACACAAGCCCAAGAAGUCUUGCAAGCGACGGGAGCCAAUUCAGGCCAGUACCGCCAGGGAGGCCAUCGAGAAGAUGCUGGAGCAGAAGAAGAUCUCCAGCAAGAUCAAUUAUAGCGUGCUCCGGGGCCUCAGCAGCGCCGGCGGGGGCAGUCCGCACAGGGAGGAUGCACAGCCCGAGCAUAGCGCCAGUGCCAGGAAGCUGUCACGAAGGAGGACGCCGGCCAGCAGAAGUGGGGCUGACCCUGUGACCAGUGUGGGGAAAAGGAGGGGCUGGGACAAUCCGUGGGGUCGGUGCCUUCUCCAGCCUGGGUUCGGGAAGAAGAGUCCCCAGCCCUGCCGCCCUGUGCCUGCUCUGCGCACCCUGGCUGCAUUGCCGUCUCUGCUGAGGUGAUGGGUGAGAGCAGCACACUGCUGAGGAAGGAGGAUGUGGGUGGAGAACGUGGCUGAGGGACGUCAAAGGCGGGAUGUGCUGGCCUCAGCGCACAGGGUCACGAGGCUCUGCAGCUCCAUGCAGGGCCGCCUUGGAGUGGGUCGGCCUCUGUGCACAGCUUGCCGCUGGGUGGCGGCUGCAGGCUCUCCUGACGAGGCCAUGGGCAGCUGGGCUCACCUGCUGCGUCUUGGGGGCCUGUGGCUGGUCCAUGUGUCCCUCUGGCAGUGGAGAUGGGGUUGGCGGCUUAGCUUCUGGGUCCACCCUUUGGUGGUUCCGACCUUCACUCCACCCCACCGAGUCUCCGGGCUGGGUGUGUCUGCUGGUCCUACUGCUUCUUGGGAUCUCUUGCGUUGUCUCCAGCUGCUUCCGCCUGUGGGGCAGUGCUGACUCUCGGCAGCCCCGUCAGGGCCUCCUGUUGUUUGCGGUAUUUGCGGUGGUUUCUCCUUGGCCUUUUGAGCUGCUAGGCUGGCCACUGCACCCCGCGAGAGUUGGCUGUGCUGUGGCCCUGCCCCUGCCCCUCCCCUGGGGUGCCCAGGUGCUACUCUGUGAGGGAGCCUGACCUCCUGGCAGGCUGGUGCUUCUCAGCCGGCGUCUCAGCCCCUCAGGAGGGCCGCAUGGGCUGUCUCCUCCACAUCAGCCAUGCACUGGUCCUCUGGGGGUGCAUUCCUAGCACAGCUCCUGGCAUGCGUAGGAGGUCAGUGGGGCAGAGGUGAAGUCAGGGCAGGUCUGUGGCUCGGUUCCCCUGUGCCUGAGCACUCCCAGGUCCGAUCUGAGGCUUUAGUCUCCGUGUCCUCUGCCUGCCUAGCCAGCCUCUGUCAGCGCUGGAGGUGGGGGUCCUGUCCCAGUUGGGUGAUUCUGGUGCCUGGUGACAGGGUUCACAGCCCCCUCUGUCACAUCUGACCAGCUGGCCCAGACAGGGCCCGGGUGUGCAUGUGUGUCUCUCUGUGUGUGUAUACAUGUACAUGCAGUGCGUGUAUGCCUGUAUCUGUGUGCAUGCAGUGUGUGCCUGUGUCUGUGCGCAUGCAGUAUUUGUGUGCAUGUGUGUGUGUGUGCCUGUGUCUGUGUACGCAGUGUGUGUGCCUGUGUCUGUAUGCCUGCAGCGUGUGUGUGCAUGUGUGUGUGCGCCUGUGUAUGCAGUGUGUGUGCAUGUGUGUGUGUGCCUGUGUCUGUGUAUGCAGUGUGUGUGUGCCUGUCUGCGUAUGCAGUGUGUGUGUGCCUGUGUCUGUAUGCCUGCAGCGUGUGUGUGCAUGUGUGUGUGUGCCUGUGUCUGUGUAUGCAGUGUGUGUGCAUGUGUGUGUGCCUGUGUAUGCAGUGUGUGUGCAUGUGUGUGUGUGCAGUGUGUGUGCAUGUGUAUGUGCCUGUGUCUGUGUAUGCAGUGUGUGUGUGUGCAUGUGUGUGUGUGCCUGUGUGCAUGCAGUAUUUGUGUGCAUGUGUGUGUGUGCCUGUGUAUGCAGUGUGUGUGUGCCUGUGUCUGUGUAUGCAGUGUGUGUGUGCCUGUUUCUGUGUAUGCAGUGUGUGUGCGCCUGUGUCUGUGUGCCUGCAGUGUAUGUGUGCAUGUGUGUGUGCCUGUGUCUGUGCAUGCAGUGCGUAUGCACACAGUACGUGUGUGCGUUGGUGCACUCAGUACGUGUGUGUGUGCAUGUGUUCUGGUGUCUGCACACAGUGUGUGCCUGUAUCUGUGACUGCACAUAGUGUGUGUGCAUGUGUGUAAGUUUUUGUGUGCAAAUGCAGGUGUGCACGCCUAUGUGUCUCUCUGUGCAUGCAGUGUGUGUGCAUGCAACAUGUGUACCUGUAUGUCUACAGAUUGUGGUGUGCAGGUCUUUGUCUCUAUGUACACGUGUGUGCAUGCAUGUGUCUGUAUACACUGUGUUUCUCUGUGUGCGUGGGGCGUGUGUGUGUGUCUUAAGUCUCUCAACUGUGUGCAGUGUGUGUGCAUCUGUGAGUCUGUGUGCACACACAUCUGCGUGUUCGUGCACUGCUUCCUGCUUUAGAAACCCAUCAGUCUUCCCCCCAACAUGGCCAUGAUCUGAUUCGGGAAUAUUUAGUGUUCUAAGACGGAAGCAUGAAGACCUCAGGGCUGGGGACCCCCCACACUCCCACCCCCACUCAGGCCUGGGCAGCUCAGGCAGUUCCAGCGGGGCAGGGGAGAGGGGGUCUACCUGGGGACAGAAGGGCUUGUCCCGGUUGCCCUUGCAGCCCAUGGGGGCAGCUUUUCACCCACACUCGGGUGAGGAAAAAGGGAUUUGGACCACUUGGAAAGAGGCUGAGGCUCCGACGUGGGGAGGGGUGGUGGGGAGGGACCAUCAAGGAGGGGUUCAGCUGAGGAGGCACUGCCUCAGCCCAGCGACCACAGCGUUCCUCAGCAGCAGCUGUGCUGCCUUGGGUGGCCCAGGCAUGGCAGUCCCUCCUUGCUGUGGGGGAACCAGCCUGAGCUGCACCCCCUUUCUCUUUGGCUGCCGGUGGCUGCCUAGCCCAUCUCCCUCUGGCCACCUGCCCCUGGUCCUGCGUCAUGAUGCAUGCUUCCCCUGAUGACAGACAACUGCAGAACCUGAGCUGGGCCACUCAGGGGUGUGGGCAGCUGAGCCACGCAGGGGUGUGGGCAGCUGAGCCAUGCAGGGGUGUGGGCAGCUGAGCCACGCAGGGGUGUGGGCAGCUGAGCCACGCAGGGGUGGGCCAUGCAUGGGUGUGGGCAGCUGAGCCACACAGGGAUGUGGGCAGCCGCUCCCUCCGAGCUUGUCUCCUCCUCACUCUGUGGUCACUCGGGCUGCUUUGACCCUCGGGGUCUUCCUCUAGCCCAUGCAGAUCAGUCUGUCCUCAUGCCUGAGCGUCCCACUCUGGGGACAGGCAGAGGGGCCAGUGUGGGCUGUGGGCCCCAGCGCCCAUAUCUGGAAGGGGGACAAAGUGGGGGCCCACCAGAUGAGCUGCCCUCUUGCCUGCUUACAGGCCCCAGGAUCCCCCCAGGCUGGGCUGGGGCCGAGCUUCAGCCAAGCGGGGUCAGCAGGUGCUGGCGCGGCUGCGAGAGGGAGCAGCCUGAGCCCAACAGUGGGUUUGCGUGAACAAUGGGCCGCAGCGCCCCACAUCCUCAGGCCCCUGGCUGGGGACCCCCGUACAGGCCAAAGCCAUGGCCGAGGUGAUGCCAGGUGGGAGCUUGUUCUCCAGGCGCUCUCAGGCCCUCCCGUGUGGCCUGGCUGCCUCAGGUUCACACAGGAUACUGCGUGGAAGAGGGGGAAGCCCUUGAGACAGGCCCCCAGCUAGCCCGCAGACCCCAGGAGCCCUUGCGGUUCUGCACUCAUGAACACUACGCACCCUCUCUCCAGCCGGGUUCUGCAGGAGUAGGGAGCUUUCUGGCCCCCCAGGGUGAGGCCUGGCACAGCUGCUUCCUGGUUCUGGAAAAGCUGGACUUGUCUGUCAGGACCUUGGGUCAGUGCAGCAGGACCUUGUGGCUUGAAUUUCAGCCUGUCCUCAGUGCCAGGUGGGGGAGGGAGGGUGUGUCCCUGCAGGAAGCGCACCCUCCUAACAGCACCGCUCUCCCUGUAGCCCCGUAUUCCUGCCCGCCAGCAUCUGCUCCUCUCUAGCUAAGGUACAGUCUGCCAAAGUCAAAGAAACUGCCUCUUCCAGAGGUUGCAGUGGGCCGAGAUCGCGUCACUGCACUCUAGCCUGGCGACAGAGCAAGAUUCCGUCUCAGAAAAAAAAAAAAGAAAAAAACUACCUCUCCUUGAGCCAGCGGGGUCUCAGGGCCCUUCUCAAUGGGGGCCUGCUGGCCUCACCUUCCAGAGCAUGAAUCUCCUGGGGACUUAGUCCCACCGGCCAAGAUCAGGCCUCCCACCCAACUGCCAGGCCUGCCUCCUGGAGCGCCAGCCACUUCUGGAGAGACCACAGUGGGGUGUCUCAUUGAGGUCAGCCUGCUGAGAAGCCCCGCUGCAGGGCCAGCUGCCAUCCCCAGAGGCCCCCACUCCACUGCACAGUGGGCCUGGGGAUGGGAGUGGGGAGGGCGGAGCAGCAGCUGUCAGGCUCCAGGAAGCAGGCUGGAGGCCUGGCCUGAGGAUACAGCACCACCAGGAGCCCUGGUGUCCAGACUGUCUCCAGUCUGGAGAGGGACCACAUGGGGAGCCCGGGGCCUCAGCCUGGCUCACACCUGCUAUCAGCUUCACCCCGAGCAGAGCUCCACGUCUAGAUGUUCUGCUAAGGUCCACCUGUCAUGGGGUCCCUUCCCAGUGUCCCGAGGGUUCAUCUGACACGUCAGAGCCAGGCAGGGCCCUGCCUCAGGCCCCCUACCGCCUCCCCACACAGCUGUGCCCUGGAGGGAAGGGCUCUGCCCCGCUGCGUCCUUCCCCACAGGCCCUGAGCCCUCUCAUUGCCCGCCCGACAGCCCUGUGUGUCCGUGCUGGAGGUUGUGGGUAAUGCCUGCGUCCUCUCCCCUGGGCCCCCCUGUCUCCCUGGGGGGACCAGCAGUCUCCAAGAAGACUUGGCAUGUGGAAGGCACCUUUGGCCUUUGUGUGUGGCGGGCCGGCGAGCAGGCCCUGUGCAGGGUGUUGUCAGCAGAUGUAGGGAUUGCCCUGGGCCUGGUGAGGGUUGGGGAAGCACUCUCGGGUCUGACAGUGUCCCUUCACCCUCCCUCCCCUCCUCCCUGAGUGAGGUAGGGCACCAGGCAGCUCCUUGAGGGCUCAGGCACUGUUGGAAGGGGAGUGGGCUGGGGAGCGGGGCGUCUGCAGCUUCUGUGUUUGUGUCGAGUGCUGCUCGCUGUUGAGAAUGUGAACGGGUCAGAGCUCUGUGUUGAUGUGCAGUGAGCACUGAUGGAGCACACAGAACCUGGACGCAGAACCAGGCUUCCAAAGGGACAGAGAAACAGUCAAUUAACACUGGGAAAGGGAAGAUGGGCAAAAGGGAACAAGUGGGCAGGCGUUCGGGAGCCUGGGCUGAGGCCGCCAUGCUGUGCUU